GCAGUCCAUGGGGCAGCGCCUAAGUGUCUGAGCACACUUAAGAAUCUCUAGUGGUUUAUGACCCAGACUUUGCCCUACCACCUCAGUCUUCUGAAUGUUCUCUUCCCUGGACCCUGCUCCAGACACUUUAAAUUCAGAAGAGGAAAAUGUGCCCAGCCUGCCUGGAGAAAAGUGUCUGCUCCUAGCCAAGAUCUCCUCAUCACAAAGAAUGGGAAUGACCUUUGACUUUAAACAAAUCCAGACUCCAGUUUUACCCUGAAUUGUUGGGGGAACAUUUUGUUUUUUUUUUCUUUUUAGUAUUUUCAAUUCUUCCAUGUCUUAGUUUUUAGGGUGUUGACCUGUGUUAAUCCAGGCUAUCUUCUAGCUAUAUCUGGUUUCCUCAGGUGGAAAAUGUUAAAUAUAGUUAAUAUAAAAUUUCACUCUAGAAUCUGCUAGAAAUGACGGAGGCAAAGUUAAUGUAUAUAUAAAAAAAUCCACCAGUGACUGGUGGCCAGUAGGCUUUCAAUAAUUGUGAAGUCCCUUCUACCCCCUUGAAAGUACUGUGUUUCUCCCCUAAGCAGCACAUUGUGUGUGGUGGUUUCAUGGUUAAAAGUUUAGACAGACCCAGCAAAUCUCUCUUCUCUUUUACUUCCUAAGUGUGUGACCUUGGACAAGUUACCUUCCCUCUCAGAGCUGAAUUUUCCUCAGUUGUAAAAUAGAGAGAAUUAGAGUAUUCAUCUCACAGGAUAAUUGUGAGACUUAAAUAAGAGAAUGCAUGUAAAAUGGUUAACAUAGGGCUUAGAAUGUAGAAAAAAAGUCCUUUGUUUUAUUGCCAAUUUUAUUUUUACUUAUGACUAAGCAGCCAUGACCUCAGAAUAAUAGUCAGGGCUGACAAUUGUGCUUCAGAGCAAGAAGGGGAAGAGGUGGUGAGAUGGAGGCUCUUUCAAUUUCUACCUCAUUUCUUAAAUGGAGCUGUUGAAAUCUACCCAUGAGCUUUGGCUGGCCACACUGACAGUGUUCUCCUCUCAGCAAAGACCAAUUAGCAAGUCCUGAUAACAGAAGUACAACCCACCCCCUUGUAAUUCCUCCUGAGAUCCUAACCAGGAUUUGUAAAACACCCGGAUAUGGGUAAAGAACCAUCCCGGGUUUUGUAUCAAACCAGGCCCCAGAGGAACAGGACAUUCCAGUAGUUUUGUUUCUGGAAAAGAGGGCACCCAGCCCUUCCCCCUCCCUCAUCCUCCCAUCCCAGUAAACCCUGCCAAAUUGGAAUCCUGGACUUAAUUUAGGAGAAAGGCCCUGUAACCAAGAUACUGACUGAACAUGGCUGGCGGACUCAGGCUGGGGUCUGCAGUGCAGCAUUAAUGGGCCGCUGACAUGAAUAUGGAGUAGUUUUCUCUAGCAAAGCAGUUUUUAUUUGCCUGUUUCCCAGAGUAAUGUGGGCCAUGGAGUCAGGCCACCUCCUCUGGGCUCUGCUGUUCAUGCAGUCCUUGUGGCCUCAACUGACUGAUGGAGCCACUCGAGUCUACUACCUGGGCAUCCGGGAUGUGCAGUGGAACUAUGCUCCCAAGGGAAGAAAUGUCAUCACGAACCAGCCUCUGGACAGUGACAUAGUGGCUUCCAGCUUCUUAAAGUCUGACAAGAACCGGAUAGGGGGAACCUACAAGAAGACCAUCUAUAAAGAAUACAAGGAUGACUCAUACACAGAUGAAGUGGCCCAGCCUGCCUGGUUGGGCUUCCUGGGGCCAGUGUUGCAGGCUGAAGUGGGGGAUGUCAUUCUUAUUCACCUGAAGAAUUUUGCCACUCGUCCCUAUACCAUCCACCCUCAUGGUGUCUUCUACGAGAAGGACUCUGAAGGUUCCCUAUACCCAGAUGGCUCCUCUGGGCCACUGAAAGCUGAUGACUCUGUUCCCCCGGGGGGCAGCCAUAUCUACAACUGGACCAUUCCAGAAGGCCAUGCACCCACCGAUGCUGACCCAGCGUGCCUCACCUGGAUCUACCAUUCUCAUGUAGAUGCUCCACGAGACAUUGCAACUGGCCUAAUUGGGCCUCUCAUCACCUGUAAAAGAGGAGCCCUGGAUGGGAACUCCCCUCCUCAACGCCAGGAUGUAGACCAUGAUUUCUUCCUCCUCUUCAGUGUGGUAGAUGAGAACCUCAGCUGGCAUCUCAAUGAGAACAUUGCCACUUACUGCUCAGAUCCUGCUUCAGUGGACAAAGAAGAUGAGACAUUUCAGGAGAGCAAUAGGAUGCAUGCAAUCAAUGGCUUUGUUUUUGGGAAUUUACCUGAGCUGAACAUGUGUGCACAGAAACGUGUGGCCUGGCACUUGUUUGGCAUGGGCAAUGAAAUUGAUGUCCACACAGCAUUUUUCCAUGGACAGAUGCUGACUACCCGUGGACACCACACUGAUGUGGCUAACAUCUUUCCAGCCACCUUUGUGACUGCUGAGAUGGUGCCCUGGGAACCUGGUACCUGGUUAAUUAGCUGCCAAGUGAACAGUCACUUUCGAGAUGGCAUGCAGGCACUCUACAAGGUCAAGUCUUGCUCCAUGGCCCCUCCUGUGGACCUGCUCACAGGCAAAGUUCGACAGUACUUCAUUGAGGCCCAUGAGAUUCAAUGGGACUAUGGCCCGAUGGGGCAUGAUGGGAGUACUGGGAAGAAUUUGAGAGAGCCAGGCAGUAUCUCAGAUAAGUUUUUCCAGAAGAGCUCCAGCCGAAUUGGGGGCACUUACUGGAAAGUGCGAUAUGAAGCCUUUCAAGAUGAGACAUUCCAAGAGAAGAUGCAUUUGGAGGAAGAUAGGCAUCUUGGAAUCCUGGGGCCAGUGAUCCGGGCUGAGGUGGGUGACACCAUUCAGGUGGUCUUCUACAACCGUGCCUCCCAGCCAUUCAGCAUGCAGCCCCAUGGGGUCUUUUAUGAGAAAGACUAUGAAGGCACUGUGUACAAUGAUGGCUCAUCUUACCCUGGCUUGGUUGCCAAGCCCUUUGAGAAAGUAACAUACCGCUGGACAGUCCCCCCUCAUGCCGGUCCCACUGCUCAGGAUCCUGCUUGUCUCACUUGGAUGUACUUCUCUGCUGCAGAUCCCAUAAGAGACACAAAUUCUGGCCUGGUGGGCCCGCUGCUGGUGUGCAGGGCUGGUGCCUUGGGUGCAGAUGGCAAGCAGAAAGGGGUGGAUAAAGAAUUCUUUCUUCUCUUCACUGUGUUGGAUGAGAACAAGAGCUGGUACAGCAAUGCCAAUCAAGCAGCUGCUAUGUUGGAUUUCCGACUGCUUUCAGAGGAUAUUGAGGGCUUCCAAGACUCCAAUCGGAUGCAUGCCAUUAAUGGGUUUCUGUUCUCUAACCUGCCCAGGCUGGACAUGUGCAAGGGUGACACAGUGGCCUGGCACCUGCUCGGCCUGGGCACAGAGACUGAUGUGCAUGGAGUCAUGUUCCAGGGCAACACUGUGCAGCUUCAGGGCAUGAGGAAGGGUGCAGCUAUGCUCUUUCCUCAUACCUUUGUCAUGGCCAUCAUGCAGCCUGACAACCUUGGGACAUUUGAGAUUUAUUGCCAGGCAGGCAGCCAUCGAGAAGCAGGGAUGAGGGCAAUCUAUAAUGUCUCCCAGUGUCCUGGCCACCAAGCCACCCCUCGCCAACGCUACCAAGCUGCAAGAAUCUACUAUAUCAUGGCAGAAGAAGUAGAGUGGGACUAUUGCCCUGACCGGAGCUGGGAACGGGAAUGGCACAACCAGUCUGAGAAGGACAGUUAUGGUUACAUUUUCCUGAGCAACAAGGAUGGGCUCCUGGGUUCCAGAUACAAGAAAGCUGUAUUCAGGGAAUACACUGAUGGUACAUUCAGGAUCCCUCGGCCAAGGACUGGACCAGAAGAACACUUGGGAAUCUUGGGUCCACUUAUCAAAGGUGAAGUUGGUGAUAUCCUGACUGUGGUAUUCAAGAAUAAUGCCAGCCGCCCCUACUCUGUGCAUGCUCAUGGAGUGCUAGAAUCUACUACUGUCUGGCCACUGGCUGCUGAGCCUGGUGAGGUGGUCACUUAUCAGUGGAACAUCCCAGAGAGGUCUGGCCCUGGGCCCAAUGACUCUGCUUGUGUUUCCUGGAUCUAUUAUUCUGCAGUGGAUCCCAUCAAGGACAUGUAUAGUGGCCUGGUGGGGCCCUUGGCUAUCUGCCAAAAGGGCAUCCUGGAGCCCCAUGGAGGACGGAGUGACAUGGAUCGGGAAUUUGCAUUGUUGUUCUUGAUUUUUGAUGAAAAUAAGUCUUGGUAUUUGGAGGAAAAUGUGGCAACCCAUGGGUCCCAGGAUCCAGGCAGUAUUAACCUACAGGAUGAAACUUUCUUGGAGAGCAAUAAAAUGCAUGCAAUCAAUGGGAAACUCUAUGCCAACCUUAGGGGUCUUACCAUGUACCAAGGAGAACGAGUGGCCUGGUACAUGCUGGCCAUGGGCCAAGAUGUGGAUCUACACACCAUCCACUUUCAUGCAGAGAGCUUCCUCUAUCGGAAUGGCGAGAACUACCGGGCAGAUGUGGUGGAUCUGUUCCCAGGGACUUUUGAGGUUGUGGAGAUGGUGGCCAGCAACCCUGGGACAUGGCUGAUGCACUGCCAUGUGACUGACCAUGUCCAUGCUGGCAUGGAGACCCUCUUCACUGUUUUUUCUCGAACAGAACACUUAAGCCCUCUCACCGUCAUCACCAAAGAGACUGAAAAAGCAGUGCCCCCCAGAGACAUUGAAGAAGGCAAUGUGAAGAUGCUGGGCAUGCAGAUCCCCAUAAAGAAUGUUGAGAUGCUGGCCUCUGUUUUGGUUGCCAUUAGUGUCACCCUUCUGCUCGUUGUUCUGGCUCUUGGUGGAGUGGUUUGGUACCAACAUCGACAGAGAAAGCUACGACGCAAUAGGAGGUCCAUCCUGGAUGACAGCUUCAAGCUUCUGUCUUUCAAACAGUAACAUCUGGAGCCUGGAGAUAUCCUCAGGAAGCACAUCUGUAGUGCACUCCCAGCAGGCCAUGGACUAGUCACUAACCCCACACUCAAAGGGGCAUGGGUGGUGGAGAAGCAGAAGGAGCAAUCAAGCUUAUCUGGAUAUUUCUUUCUUUAUUUAUUUUACAUGGAAAUAAUAUGAUUUCACUUUUUCUUUAGUUUCUUUGCUCUACGUGGGCACCUGGCACUAAGGGAGUACCUUAUUAUCCUACAUCGCAAAUUUCAACAGCUACAUUAUAUUUCCUUCUGACACUUGGAAGGUAUUGAAAUUUCUAGAAAUGUAUCCUUCUCACAAAGUAGAGACCAAGAGAAAAACUCAUUGAUUGGGUUUCUACUUCUUUCAAGGACUCAGGAAAUUUCACUUUGAACUGAGGCCAAGUGAGCUGUUAAGAUAACCCACACUUAAACUAAAGGCUAAGAAUAUAGGCUUGAUGGGAAAUUGAAGGUAGGCUGAGUAUUGGGAAUCCAAAUUGAAUUUUGAUUCUCCUUGGCAGUGAACUACUUUGAAGAAGUGGUCAAUGGGUUGUUGCUGCCAUGAGCAUGUACAACCUCUGGAGCUAGAAGCUCCUCAGGAAAGCCAGUUCUCCAAGUUCUUAACCUGUGGCACUGAAAGGAAUGUUGAGUUACCUCUUCAUGUUUUAGACAGCAAACCCUAUCCAUUAAAGUACUUGUUAGAACACUGAAAGACUGAAUUUGGUGAUUUUUGACAGUCUCUGUGGCUUCUGUCACUGUGAUUGAAACAGAAAAUACUUAGGGGGUGAGUGAGUAUAGUAUGUAUUUGUCUAGCCUUUGUAGAACCUACAAGUUUUUGUUUUAGAGAUGAGGAAGCUGUUCCAGAGGAAGCAUCAAAGAGUGCUGGGUACCACCCUAGAAAAGGAGCUGUCGCAUAAAUGACAAAAAUUUUCUGAGUGUCAAGAAAAUUUGCCAGAGGGAAAUAGAAGUCUGAGACGAGACUCAAACCUGUCCAGUGGGCCAGGGGAAGUAGGACCAUAUCUUAUGGGGCCUUUUUGGCAGUGGUGGUGUGAAAGGUCUAGUUGCAACUUUGGGGGCUUCCUUAUAGGAUGGAGUCAUUCUUUCUGGUAUUUUACAGCAAUAUUCCUUUGUUACAUGCAAAUUUGAGCCAAAUAUUGGUUAGAGAGCACAGAUAAGUGAUAAAUUUUAGAUUGGGUAAGAUGGCCCACCCCACUGCAAUAUCCAUAAUAUUGUACCACAUGGCAAGUGGAGAACAGAAGAGGUAUCAAGGAGAGAAAAGAUGAUAACUAUGUACUGUUUUACACUUUAAAAAGCAUUUUAAUUCUUGAUUGCGUUUGGAUUACCUCAGGGCAAGUCAUUUUACAUUUGAGUAAUGUUAUCCAUUUAUACAUUUGAGUGAACAAAAGCUUAUGGACAUUAAGUAACUUCAUCCAAGAUCCCUCAGGUAGAAGUUGAGCAGGGAUUCAUGUAUUCAUCUGUUUGACUCCAAAUACCUAUUUCAUCCUCAUAUAUCAUGGAAACAUCCACUAAUCUCCAUCCACCUUACCCAUAUUGAUUCCAACUUUUCUGUCUGUCCAGCAAUCUGUCUGUCUAGGUAGCAAUCUCUUGAAGAUAAAAUGUAGAAACUCACAGAGCUGGUGUUCAGUUACGAUAUAAGUUUGGAGGAGAAAACACAAUCCAGAAGCUAUGAUUCCUCUUGUUUUUCCAUGGUCAAUGGGUUUCUGGAGAGCUUUACUGAGAAUCUCAGAAAUAAAGUGUGGGUGGAAGGGGGAUUUAGAUGGCUAGUUAUCCAAGAGUUAGUGUUUAGGCCAUUGCAGAAUCAAUGAUUUAACAGCAGCAGAACUGUUUUGGCCUGCAGUUAACAUGAAUGUUAAUGAAGACCAAGUACAUGCUAGGAAUUCCAGUCAAUUAAUGGUUAUAAUUUACAUGCAACUAGGAGGUUCUUAGCUUGGUCUCAGUUAUAACUCUAAGAGACUAGGAGAGGUAGAUGAGAUGGAAUGCAUUUCUUCUUAUUUUGUAAUCCUGCUCCAGGUCAAGGAAUAGAAACUCAGAGCCCAUGUAUUUAAGAAAGAAAUGUAUUUUUGUGGUAAGUUUGCUCCAAGUAGGGAUACAAGUAUCUAUUUUUGACAAUCAAGUGACAUUGCCAUCUAUUCAGUUGCUCAAGCUGGAAAUUAUCAGUGUCAACA